GGUGCCGUUUCCCGGUUCGCUCGGCCGCGGUCGCUAUGGAGGAGCCGGAGAUGCAGCUCAAGGGGAAGAAAGUCACGGACAAGUUCACUGAGAGCGUCUACGUCCUGGCCAACGAGCCAUCCGUGGCCCUGUACCGGCUGCAGGAGCAUGUGCGUCGCUCCCUCCCCGAGCUGGCCCAGCACAAGGCAGACAUGCAGCGUUGGGAGGAGCAGAGCCAGGGAGCCAUCUACACUGUGGAGUACGCCUGCAGCGCCGUGAAGAACCUGGUGGACAGCAGCGUCUACUUCCGCAGCGUGGAGGGUCUGCUCAAACAGGCCAUCAGCAUCCGGGACCAUAUGAAUGCCAGUGCCCAGGGCCACAGGUAGCUCCUGGGACCGCCCGCCCCCACUGCCACUCCCAGCUGCAAGGACCGUCUCUCAGCUGCGCUGGGAACCGCUGCUUCUCGCUUAUUAGAAAACUGUCUCUUUCCUUUUGUCCUGGUGUCUGGUGACCUCCUCUUGUCCUGUGGCAUCUAUAACCUGAGUUCAGUCACUUAAUACCGAGGUCCUGCGCUCUGCUGUGUGCCUGGCCCUGGGCUGGGCACUGGGGACAUAGCAGUGACCGAGACAGACAGGCUCACAAGGAGACAUACGACAACCAGGUAAACAUGGCAGACAAGAGCAUGUCAGAUGCGCUGUGAAGAACACUGCGGGGCCCCUCCUAGGAGGUGGCAUGAGUUACAUGCAGACAGAGACGAUCCGGGGGCAGACGGAGUUCCAUGUGGGGCAGUGGUGAGGGCAGACGCUCUGGGGCUGGGAUCCCUGGGAGUGUUCGAGAAGCACCGAGAAGGCUUCUGUGGCUGGAGCCGGCCAGCUGGGGGAGAUGGGGCCAGGGAGAUGGCAGGGGCCUCUCCCUGUCCCAGGACCCAGAGCCAAGGGAGGCUUUAAGCCCAGGACCAGGGGUCUGAAAACGAAAAGCACUCACAGUCCUUGAACAUUGGAAAGAGAAUUUUUGAAGAGUAGCCCUUCUUUUUGUUUUUGUUGGCAUUCUAAGUUAAUAAACACGCUUAUGAACACACA